CUCCCAAGGCCGGCGGCGGCAUGGCGGCCAGGCAGAUCUGGGCACGGACGGGUGCCGCGCUCUGCAGGCAACCUUCCGCCGCCCCGCCGCCAGCACCUCUCUGGGUAAGAGCUGGGUUCCGACAGCAGCUCAGCUUAACCCUCUGCCCUGCUAACGAGGGAAACUGCGGCGGCUCCGCGCCCAGCACGCCCGGUAGGCCGGAGAGAGCGGCGAGGCCUUCGGUGAGCGAAGAGUUAACCGCGGCGGAGCGACAGAUCGCGGAGCUGCACGCUGCCGCCUGCGCGGCUGGCCAGCUAAACUAUGUGGAUCCAGCUACUGGCUAUGUGGUGCUCACACAGAUUGCCCACUUGCAAAGAGGUGAAUGUUGUGGCUCUGCGUGCAGACAUUGUCCAUAUGGUCAAGUCAAUGUUAAAGAUCCAUCUAAAAAGAAGCAAUUCAAUUCAUAUUUUUAUGUUUGACAAGAAUUUCAUCUCUGUUCCCUAACUGUGCUUGUAUUUUUUAAAAAAUAAAGCCCCAAUUCAGAAUUGCUGGAUUAUUAGUACUUGAACACUAGUUUAAUCCUAAAUACAUAUAUUAAAAGAACAUCAAUAAAAUGAAAAA